AGAAGAUGAGAGAAUGGGUGGCUGUAUGCACAGUACCCAGGACAAAUCUCUCCACUUGGAAGGAGAUCCCAAUCCUUCUGCAGCCCCAACAUCCACCUGCGCACCUAGGAAAAUGCCCAAAAGGAUUUCAAUAUCCAAACAACUGGCUUCAGUGAAAGCUCUGAGGAAGUGCUCAGAUCUGGAAAAAGCUAUUGCCACCACUGCUCUGAUUUUCAGAAAUUCUUCUGACUCUGAUGGUAAACUUGAAAAAGCUAUUGCCAAAGAUCUGCUGCAAACCCAAUUUAGGAAUUUCGCAGAGCUCCCCUUCACCUUCUACCAUGAGUGGAAGCAGCCUGAGGUCCUCACCACAUGCAGAUGCCUGAUCUUGAACUUUCCAGCCAUCAGAAUUGGACAAGAAACCAAGCCAAAAUACAGAGAGAUCCUUUCUGAACUUGAUGAGCACACAGAAAAUAAGCUAGAUUUUGAAGACUUCAUGAUCUUGCUCUUAAGCAUCACUGUCAUGUCAGAUCUGCUACAAAAUAUACGGAAUGUAAAAAUUAUGAAAUGAACAGUUUUAAAUAUGCUGUAUAAAAUAAUGGCAAAAGACAGUGUUAUUAAAAUGUUUCCAUCUUAUUUUUGAUUAAUUGAAUAUAUCUAUCAUGCAUCUGAAAUUGCCUAGGAUGGUUCUGAUUGCUGGUAUUCAGAUCCAAUGUAACUCCAAAUAUUUACCCAUACACUUCAAGAAUGUUUGAAUGAUAAGGUCUCUGUGUGCUUUACAAUAGGAUAGAUUUGAUACCACUGAAUAAUAAAUGGCUUUUGCUGAGUCAGUAGCGACCUAGAGCACUCUACUUAUAGUCAUUGAGUCACUCAUUUAUUCACUAAACAUUUGUUGAGCAUCUACUUGAUGGAACUGCUGAGGAUACAGUAAUGAAUUGGCCAGGCAAUUCCUUCCUUCAGACAUGUUUGCAGAAGUCUAGCAGAAGAGAUAGACAUUGAACAAUUUUUAAAUAAUUGCAUACACAGUAUAAUUAGAAUUGAAAUAAGGGCUAUAGGAUGCUAAAAGAGAUUAUCACCUGAUCGGAGUUCAAAGGUCAGAAAAGCUUUACUGACAUUCUAUAAAAAGCAAAAAAAAAAAAAUUGGUCCAUGGAUGCCAGGGAUAUGGGUGGGAAAUGGGGCUGUCCACAAAUGGCACAAGGGGAGUUUUUUAUUUUAUUUUAUUUUAUUUUAUUUUAUUUUAUUUUGAGACAGAGUUUUGCUCUUGUUGCCCAGGCUGGAGUGCAAUGGCACGAUCUCAGCUUACUGCAACCUCGAUCUCCCAGGUUCAAGUGAUUCUCCUGCCUCAGCCUCCUGAGUAGCUGGGAUUACAGGCGUGUGCCACGAUGCCAGGCUAAUUUUUUUUGUAUUUUUAGUGGAGACGGGGUUUCGCCAUGUCGGCCAGGCUGGUCUCGAACUCCUGACCUCAGGUGAUCCGCCCACAGCCUCCCAAAGUGCUGGGAUUACAGGCUUGAGCCACCAAGUCUGGCCAAGGGGACUUUUAAGGGGGCUGGAAAUGGUCUCCAUUUUGAUUGUGAGGUGGUGGCUACAAGAUUGCAUGCAUUUGUCAAACUCAUAGAACUGCACACUGAAAAGAGUGAAUUGUACUGUAUGUCAAUUAUACCUAAAUAAAUCUGACUUAACAAAAAAA